AGAACACCCAGCCCUUGAGACUUGACUAAGAAAUUAAAUCCAUGUUAUCAGCACGUUUUUAACUGGAUGUGAUAUAAGGGGAAAAUGGCUUUGUUGGCCUCAGAUAGCUGCUUUAUUAGAUGUAAUGAAGCAGGGGACAUAGAAGCAAAAAGUAAAACAGCAGGAGAAGAAGAAAUGAUCAAGAUUAGAUCCUGUGCUGAAAGAGAAACCAAGAAAAAAGAUGACAUUCCAGAAGACAAAGGAAAUGUAAAACAAUAUGAAAUCAAUUAUGUAAAGAAAUUUCAGAGCUUCCAAGACCACAAACCUAAAAUAAGUAAAGAAGAUAGUAAAAUUCUUAAAAAGGCUCAGAAAGAUGGAUUUUUGCAUGAGACGCUUCUGGACAGGAAACACUGGCCUCCUUCAUCCUCAGUCUGUGUUGCUGGAAGUCACCCAUCUCCAAGGCCCCUUGGGAUCGACUGAGUGACCAGCAGUGAAGUUCGUCCACCUUCUAAAUGGAUGCCAUCAUCUGACGUGAUGGAGCUCAGUGGGAUGCUGCUGCCUUACCUCGCUUAGCUAGGAUGUCCCUGAUAAAGGAUGACACCAAAGCUUCAGCACAACUGGCCAAACUUGAGGUGGUCAUCUCAGCACUGAUGCUGGGCCAACAAUUAGCCCCAUUUGUACAUUUUUACAAAUUUUUGGCAAUUGCCAAGAAUUGUCCACCUUCCCUCCCCAUUGAAUUAAAGACACUUCUUGCCUCAUGGAUAGUCAGAAUACAGUCAAGGUAACAGAUGCCUUUUUUUUAACCAAGGACACAGUACAGAUCUCACAGGGACACUCCUUAUCCCCUACAGAGAGUUCCAGACACUACUGAUGGUGACCAAGGCAACAUUUCAACAGAAAACACAGUGCUAGGCUUGUGAAAGUGUCCAGUAGGGCUUCCACUGCCCCUAUAGGCUGCAGGCAGCUGCUUUAGUUGAGAGAUAGACUGAGCUCCUCGAAGAAUUCCUAUUUAAGUUACAAAGCAGCGAGUGGAUGCCCUGCUGGGUUCCACUGUUGCCACAGGCUUUGAUUACUCUUAAGUUCAUGCUUCUUAGGAAAUUGCACUUUUUACACCAGUGCUACACAGUUCCCUCAGUUGCCUUUACUGGACAUCAAGGAGUUCACAUUUUUGACAACCAUUCAGUCCUGGACAGUCCAAGGGGUGGAGGUAGCUUCGUACAGGAAUCUGCCUGCUGCGUGUGGAUCAGUAAUAUCAGAAUUGCCCAACAACUCACUGGAGAUAUGAAAACCAAUGCAUGGGGGAUGCAUGACGUCACCCAAAUAUUUAUGAACACGCUUGUGCUGCCAGAGACCCCAGAUCUCUAAACCAAUGCAUGGGAAAUGCAUGACGUCACCCAAAUAUUUACGAACAGGCUUGUGCUGCCAGAGACCCCAGAUCACUUUUCCUGCCUCCUGCUAAAUAAAUGGGGGCAGUAGAUUUGCAUCGGUUUCCACAUUACAUUACUCAUAACUGUGGCCUUCCUAAUUUCUCAUGUCCCUAAGCACUUAUUACAAUGUCUCAGCAGCUUUCUCUCAGCCUCUCAAAAUAUUAGUCAUCAUGAAAAUAAAUGUCUGAUGUUAAAGCA